GCCGCCUCCCGGAGCCAGGGCUGCGGGGUGUGGGGCGGGGAGGAGGCGCUCUGCUGUGGAGCCUGCCGCCGAGUGACCGCUCGACUACAAAUAGCCUGGGGAGCUGCGGGGAGGGCAUCUUGACCUGGGCCAGGACAACCUGCCUUGGGUCGGAGCAGGUUCCAGGGAGAAUCAGAGAUGGUGAAUUCCCAGCCUGCGUCUUAUGCCUUCUCCCCAUCCGCUGCUGCGUCCUCAUCCUGGCUUCCCACCGCUGAGCUCCGCGUGUGCGGCACCCACCUCAGGGGGCCUUUACCUGGUCCAGAAGUGCAUCUGUCUUUGCACCAGAUUAUUGGGGACCUCAAGCGUCUGCUCCAGCGGCUCUCCUGUGGCAUGUGACUUCCCCUUCUCGCUCCAGCGUCCUGCCGUUUUCUACGAGAUUGUUAUUCCAGGUCAUCAAGAGAGAGGGCACAGGUACAGAGAUGCCCAUGAUUGGGGACCGAGUCUUUGUCCACUACACUGGCUGGCUAUUAGAUGGCACAAAGUUUGACUCCAGUCUGGAUCGCAAGGACAAAUUCUCCUUUGACCUGGGAAAAGGGGAGGUCAUCAAGGCUUGGGACAUUGCCAUAGCCACCAUGAAGGUGGGGGAGGUGUGCCACAUCACCUGCAAACCAGAAUAUGCCUACGGUUCAGCAGGCAGUCCUCCAAAGAUUCCCCCCAAUGCCACGCUUGUAUUUGAGGUGGAGUUGUUUGAGUUUAAGGGAGAAGAUCUGACGGAAGAGGAAGAUGGCGGAAUCAUUCGCAGAAUACAGACUCGCGGUGAAGGCUAUGCUAAGCCCAAUGAGGGUGCUAUCGUGGAGGUUGCACUGGAAGGGUACUACAAGGACAAGCUCUUUGACCAGCGGGAGCUCCGCUUUGAGAUUGGCGAGGGGGAGAACCUGGAUCUGCCUUAUGGUCUGGAGAGGGCCAUUCAGCGCAUGGAGAAAGGAGAACAUUCCAUCGUGUACCUCAAGCCCAGCUAUGCUUUUGGCAGUGUUGGGAAGGAAAAGUUCCAAAUCCCACCAAAUGCUGAGCUGAAAUAUGAAUUACACCUCAAGAGUUUUGAAAAGGCCAAGGAGUCUUGGGAGAUGAAUUCAGAAGAGAAGCUGGAACAGAGCACCAUAGUGAAAGAGCGGGGCACUGUGUACUUCAAGGAAGGUAAAUACAAGCAAGCUUUACUACAGUAUAAGAAGAUCGUGUCUUGGCUGGAAUAUGAGUCUAGUUUUUCCAAUGAGGAAGCACAGAAAGCACAGGCCCUUCGACUGGCCUCUCACCUCAACCUGGCCAUGUGUCAUCUGAAACUACAGGCCUUCUCUGCUGCCAUUGAAAGCUGUAACAAGGCCCUAGAACUGGACAGCAACAACGAGAAGGGCCUCUUCCGCCGGGGAGAGGCCCACCUGGCCGUGAAUGACUUUGAACUGGCACGGGCUGAUUUCCAGAAGGUCCUGCAGCUCUACCCCAACAACAAAGCCGCCAAGACCCAGCUGGCUGUGUGCCAGCAGCGGAUCCGAAGGCAGCUUGCCCGGGAGAAGAAGCUCUAUGCCAAUAUGUUUGAGAGGCUGGCUGAGGAGGAGAACAAGGCCAAGGCAGAGGCUUCCUCAGGAGACCAUCCCACUGACACAGAGAUGAAGGAGGAGCAGAAGAGCAACACGGCAGGGAGCCAGUCUCAGGUGGAGACAGAAGCAUAGCCCCUCUCCACCAGCCCUACUCCUGCGGCUGCCUGCCCCCCAGUCUCCCCACUCCACCCUGUUAGUUUUGUAAAAACUGAAGAAUUUUGAGUGAAUUAGACCUUUAUUUUUCUAUCUGGUUGGAUGGUGGCUUUAGGGGAAGGGGGAAAGGUGUAGGCUGGGGGAUUGAGGUGGGGAAUCAUUUUAGCUGGUGUCAGCCCCUCUUCCCUUCCUCCAUUGCACAUGAACAUAUGUCCAUCCAUAUAUAUUCAUCAGAAUGUUAAUUUAUUUUGCUCCCUCUGUUAGGUCCAUUUUCUAAGGGUAGAAGAGGCAAGUGGUAGGGAUGAGGUCUGAUAAGAACCCAGGGUGGAGAGGGAGACUCCUGGGCAGCCGUUUUCCUCAUCCUUUCCCUCUCCCAGUCCAUUUCCAAAUGUGGCCUCCAUGUGGGUGCUAGGGACAUGGGAAAAACCACUGCUAUGCCAUUUCUUCUCUCUGUUCCCUUCCUCACCCCCGACGGUGUGGCUGAUGAUGUCUUCUGGUGUCAUGGUGACCACCCCCUGUUCCCUGUUCUGGUAUUUCCCCUGUCAGUUUCCCCUCUCGGCCAGGUUGUGUCCCAAAAUCCCCUCAGCCUCUUCUCUGCACGUUGCUGAAGGUCCAGGCUUGCCUCAAGUUCCAUGCUUGAGCAAUAAAGUGGAAACAAUAAAACCUGGGUGUCAGACAACCCUUUCUGUUCAGCCUUGGAGUGGUGGGUAUGGGUGGGUACAUAAUGGGUAGUAGCACAAUCAAGGGGUCACCCACUUAGUUCCAGUUGAGCUUAAAUAAGUGAGCAUCUCAUGUAGAUGCCAUAGUUGGGCAGGAAGCAGCCCCACCAUGCAUGGCUUCCUGAGCACUGCACAGGCUGCCGCUGGGAUUUGUGUCUAUGGCUUCGCCCAAGGUUCCCAGCACUCCCUCCCUCCAGCAACCUGGCAGUUUUAGUGCCUCUGGUUUUCUUCCCUGACACUUAGGAAGACGAAAGUAUAAAGAUCUAGAAGACUGGGACACCAUGCAUGUUCAUUUUGAAGUUGGAAUUGGUCUUCUGCCUACCUCUGAUCUGGCAGAGGUAUCUGCAUUUUGGUUUGUUAACAAGGUAAAACUCCUGGUGUCACUGACCUCCUCCUGUCAGAUAACUUACAUGAUUAAGGUUAAGAGUAAAGCAGAGUGUUCACGUCCAGCUUCCUUCUCAGCCUUAACAGGAAAAGGCUUGUGCUUUUUUUCUAACUAUGCUUUGACCCUUAACUCCUAUGGCAUGAUGGGGCCCUGGGAGAAGCCAGGCAGCACAAGCCAGUCAUGCUGAGCUGCCUCCAGAUAAUCCUGGCUCCAGGCCAGAGCCCGUGUCUGCCCUCAUCCCUCUCUCCUACUGUGAGCUCUCCAGUCCUUUCCCAACAGCGAUGUGGUUGUCUGCUUAGCCACAUGCCUGUAUAGUUCCUUCCAGAAGAAAUGUAUAAUGGUGGAAGAUGUAUUUCUGUGUGAAAAUUUUCACCAAGUCAUACAACACAGCUGAUGCUGGAGCCAGGAUUAAAAUUGGGGUGUACAAGUCUCCCAGUGUGAGUAUCCCUUGAGCCCAAGACACCAAGGAUGCAGAGAACUGUGACUGUGCCACUGCACGCCAGCCUGGGCAAGAGAGUGAGACCAUCUCUUUUUUAAAAAAGUCCCUGUGUAACUGCUUUCUUACUGGGCUUACCUCACAUCACAGCCCUGUGUUUGUGGUUUGUGUCUGGGUCCUCUUGGUAUUUCAAAAGUAGUAGAUUCUUACGCCUGCAGCCAACAAUAAUCACUAACUCAAGCAUUUAUGGAGUAAGCCUAGCACUGUACUGACAGCAUCACAUGAGUGAAACUGAAUCCUUGCAACCAUCCUACAAAGAAGGUAUAACUUUAAUAACCCUAUUUACAGAUAAGAAAACCAAGACUCAGAAGUUAAAUGGAAAGGUGAGGUCUCUGAACUAAUCCAGACUCUCCCAUGAGGUUCCUUUGGCAAGUCCUGGGCUUCUGUCCUCAUCUGCAAAAUCGAAAGCAUUCCUGAGGUUUCUUCCAGCUCUGCAUCCUGUAGGAUUCCAAGAAUGUAAAACUGCAUGUAACCGUGGAACAUCUAGAGAUAAGUCUUAGUUUAUGUAACAUUAAAACUGUCUAGUGAGGAUGUUUUGUUAAAA